GUUGUUGCCCUCAGGUCGCUCCCGGGCGGGGACACGGAACCCGGCCAUGGAAGAUCCGUCGGGGGCUCGCGAGCCCCGGGCCCGGCCGAGAGAGCGGGACCCGGGACGGCGCCCCCACCCAGACCAAGGCCGCACCCACGAUCGACCGCGGGACCGACCCGGGGACCCGCGCAGGAAGCGAAGCAGCGACGGGAACCGGCGAAGGGACGGGGACCGGGACCCGGAGAGAGACCAGGAGAGGGACGGGAACCGCGACCGGAACCGGGACCGGGAGAGGGAGAGAGAGAGGGAAAGAGACCCGGACCGAGGCCCCCGCCGGGACACACACAGGGACGCGGGCCCUCGCGCAGGUGAACACGGAGUUUGGGAAAAACCGCGCCAAAGCCGGACGCGGGACGGAGCCCGGGGACUGACCUGGGACGCAGCCGCGCCUCCUGGGCCCGCGCCCUGGGAAGCCCCGGAGCCGCCGCAGCCGCAGAGGAAGGGAGACCCCGGGCGCCGCAGACCCGAAAGUGAACCCCCUUCGGAGAGAUAUCUGCCCUCGACCCCCAGGCCUGGACGAGAGGAGGUGGAAUAUUACCAGUCAGAGGCGGAAGGACUCCUGGAAUGCCACAAAUGCAAAUACUUGUGCACUGGGAGAGCCUGCUGCCAAAUGCUGGAGGUUCUCCUGAACUUGCUGAUCCUGGCCUGCAGCUCUGUGUCUUACAGUUCCACAGGGGGCUACACGGGCAUCACCAGCUUGGGGGGCAUUUACUACUAUCAGUUCGGAGGGGCUUACAGUGGCUUUGAUGGUGCUGACGGGGAGAAGGCCCAGCAACUGGAUGUCCAGUUCUACCAGCUAAAGCUGCCCAUGGUCACUGUGGCAAUGGCCUGUAGUGGAGCCCUCACAGCCCUCUGCUGCCUCUUCGUUGCCAUGGGUGUCCUGCGGGUCCCGUGGCAUUGUCCACUGUUGCUGGUGACCGAAGGCUUGUUGGACAUGCUCAUCGCGGGGGGGUACAUCCCGGCCUUGUACUUCUACUUCCACUACCUCUCUGCUGCCUAUGGCUCUCCUGUGUGUAAAGAGAGGCAGGCGCUGUACCAAAGCAAAGGCUACAGCGGUUUCGGCUGCAGUUUCCACGGAGCAGAUAUAGGAGCUGGAAUCUUUGCUGCCCUGGGCAUUGUGGUCUUUGCCCUGGGGGCUGUCCUGGCCAUAAAGGGCUACCGAAAAGUUAGGAAGCUAAAAGAGAAGCCAGCAGAAAUGUUUGAAUUUUAAGGGUUUCUAAAACGCUCUGACAGAUGCAAGUGGUGGUGGAAGGUAGUCUGAGCCACUGCCUUUCCCAAGAAUCCCUUGUUGUGGAAGUUUCCAGUGCUGGAAAAGCAGCGAGCCAGCGUUGGUGUGGUGGGCGGAGCUCCCAGUCGCAUGGAGCGGUGUUCAUGGAUGCAACAGACCCUGGCUUCUGGAGUCCUCUGUGAGUGAGGGACCAAUCAAAAUUAUUUUUCAAAAAGCAAAAAAAUGGCCGGCCUCGGCGGCUCACACCUGUAACCCCAGCACUUUGGGAGGCUGAGGUGGGUGGAUCACUUGAGGUCAGGAGCUCGAGACCAGCUUGGCCAACAUGGUGAGCCCCCGUCUCUACUAAAAUACAAAAAAAUUAGCCAGGCGUGGUGGCGGGCGCCUGUAAUCCCAGCUACUUGGGAGGCUGAGGCAGGAGAAUCGCUUGAAUCUGGGAGGCGGAGAUUGCAGUGAGCCGAGAUCCCGCCACUGCACUCCAGCCCAGGUGACAGAGCGAGACUCCAUCUCAAAAAAAAAAAAAAGCAAAAAAACUGGACCCCAAGAGCCACAAGGAAAAAGCAUGUACUACAACAGAGUGCACCUCUUCAUUCAGUAAAGGGAGGUCACCAAGAGAAUUUGAUGAACCUUACCUUCAAAGUUCCUGGGCACAGUGGCUCACACCUGUAAUCCCAGAGCUUUGGGAGGCUGAGGUAGGAGGAUUGCUUGAACCCAGGAGUUCAAGUUUGCAGUGCGCUAUGAUUGUCCCACUACACUCUAGCCUGAGCAACAGACCAAGACCGUAUUGCCAAAAUACCAAAAAAAAAAAAAGUUCAUGGAGAGCCACAUAGACAUGAGACCACACUUCAGCCUGAAUUUUUCUAAAACACAGUUGUCUCAAGCAGAUUACUCCACACGUUUUUCCACACUGAACUCUCCAGUCCUUCCACUUCCUUAAUUCUGCAAAUGGAGGGGGUGGGGACUCUUGGGAAACUACUCCUGUAAAAUUGAAGUUGGAGGUAGGCGUGGGCUGAGGAAAGAGGAAUCAGAUUAAUUCUCUGGGUUGCAAAGAGGCUAUUCUGCAAGCCCCUUACAGUGGCCCUGAAAGCUCAAUAAGUGUUUUGUACCUCUUGUAAAUGUGCCAUUGUGUGAAGCAUUAAACCCAACAUCUAGAAUUCAGGAUUCAUCCAGAAUAAAAGGAUGUAAAAUCUUUCCCAACAGAAGAGUGUUACUUUUGGUCAGACAACUUCAUGGGUUCUUACUGCACAUUAAAUUAUGACUUAUGGAACAUUGCAAUAUAUUCUCGGUCCUUAAGUUAUGACUUAUGGAACAUUACAAUAUAUUCUCGGUCCAAGUGAGUAAGUUCUUUGCUUUAUGUGAAUCCAAUAAAAAAUCCAAAGAAUUUUAAUUUGGAGUUGAUGUCCUCUUUACAAUACAUUUAUAAUAUUCUCUUAAAUACAGACAAUUUUUCACAUUUAAAAGGUGAGUUCCAUUUGAGUUUAGAAAAGGAAAUAUAUAUAUACAUGCUUGUAUAUGAUUGGAAAAUUUCUUGAAGAAUAACAUCAGAAAGUAUUAAGUUUUGCUUUUGAAGAGAAGGGGACUUUUCAUUUAUACAUGGCUUGACUGCACAUGUAUUAAUUUUAGAAAAAUAAAAAGUAAAAAAGUUGA